AAUAGCUUGACAAUGAAGUUGAAAAGACAGCAAAUCUUGUCAUUAGCAACUGGAAUCAGCAAAUUAAGGCCAAGAAGAAAUUAAUGGUUAGUACCAAGAAACAUGAAGCACUUUUCCAGCUUGUAGAAAGCUCCAAGCAAUCUAUGACUGAGAAGGAGAAGCGGAAGCUCCUCAAUAAACUGACAAAAUCAACUGAAAAGUUGGAAAAGGAAGAUGAAAAUUACUACCAAAAAAACAUGGCGGGUUAUUCUACCAGACUGAAAUGGGAAAACACACUAGAGAACUGCUACCAGGUAACCCACAGCAUCUGCCUAUAUGCCUUUUGGGUCAAAAGAGCCUGGGGAAAGUGUGUGAGUGAUUUAAGAUACCAAGACAUAUUCCUUCCUGGAAAUCUCCCUCCACUAUGGUUUGGAUAUGACAUAGUCAAGAGGCUAAUCAUGAGACUUUGUUCAGUCUGUCUUCAGAGCAUUCUGGAGCUGGAGAAGGAAAGAAUUCAACUUUUAUGCAAUAACUUAAACCAGUACAGCCAACAUAUUUCUCUUUUUGGCCAAACCCUGACCACAUGCCACACGCAGAUUCACUGUGCCAUCAGCAAGAUUGACAUUGAAAAAGAUAUCCAGGCUGUAAUGGAAGAAACUGCAAUUUUAUCUACAGAAAACAAAUCUGAGUUCCUGUUAACGGAUUACUUUGAAGAAGAUCCUAACAGUGCAAUGGAUAAAGAGAGACGAAAGUCUUUACUAAAACCAAAAUUAUUGAGACUGCAGAGAGACAUUGAAAAAGCCUCAAAAGACAAGGAAGGCCUGGAACGAAUGCUUAAAACGUACUCCAGCACCUCCUCCUUCUCUGAUGCAAAGAGCCAGAAAGACACAGCAGCGUUAAUGGAUGAGAACAAUUUGAAACUAGACCUUUUGGAAGCGAACUCCUACAAACUGUCAUCAAUGUUAGCAGAACUUGAGCAAAGACCUCAACCCAGCCAUCCUUGUAGUAAUUCCAUCUUCAGGUGGAGGGAAAAGGAGCAUACUCAUAGCUAUGUGAAAAUAUCUCGGCCUUUUUUAAUGAAGAGAUUAGAGAAUAUUGUGAGCAAGGCAUCUUCUGGUGGGCAGAGCAAUCCAGGUUCUUCAACUCCAGCCCCUGGUGCAGCCCAGCUCAGCAGCAGACUUUGCAAGGCCUUGUAUUCUUUUCAAGCCAGGCAAGAUGAUGAGUUGAAUUUGGAAAAGGGUGACAUUGUGAUUAUACACGAGAAAAAAGAAGAAGGAUGGUGGUUUGGAUCUUUGAAUGGGAAAAAAGGCCAUUUUCCUGCCGCUUAUGUGGAGGAGUUACCUUCAAAUGCUGGCAACACAGCUACAAAGGCAUAAAACAAGACUCUGAACAUACUACCUUCACACUCGGUAAUCAACAAUACAGUGUGGUUCAAAUAAGAAUAAAGUGCUCUUACCUUUACAUGUUUUUCUUUUGAAAUGGAUGGAGUUCUACCUGCAUGUCACAGCACUUUGCAUUCAUGAUUAUUAGCUUGAAACAGUCAGAAAAAAGAUGGAUGGGUGGAGACAGACAAGGAAGAGGCUCCUUGGUUCCUAGAGGAGUUUCCAAAUUCUAGGAGACCCUAGAGAUGAUCCAGUAUAACCCCUGGUGUCACAGAAACAGACGGAGUCCAAGGUGGGUUCAGCUGCUUGCCUGAAGUCAGAGUUAUCUGGUAGACAACAGCAGUGGGACUUAGAUGUCUUUUUCCUCUGGAUUUGGGUGGCAACAGAACACAGCAGGCCUAUGAGGGGGUCAAGCAGAGCCUGGGAGAUGAGGAACACAGAUCAAUUCCAAGAAGAGAGACAGGCAAUCAAGACACCAAUGAGAUCAACCCAAAUUAGGGGAUGGUAGGAUAUCUCUGACAAACCCACAGCCAAUAUC